UUUCAGGCCACAAGGGCAGCCAUUACUCAGCACUGCACUGACCUUGGGAAUUUGCUGGGCAAGGAAAAUGACGUGGCCCUGAUCAUCGAUGGCCACACCCUGAAGUACGCGCUCUCCUUCGAAGUCCGGAGGAGUUUCCUGGAUUUGGCACUCUCGUGCAAAGCGGUCAUAUGCUGCAGAGUGUCUCCUCUGCAGAAGUCUGAGAUAGUGGAUGUGGUGAAGAAGCGGGUGAAGGCCAUCACCCUCGCCAUCGGAGACGGCGCCAACGAUGUCGGGAUGAUCCAGACAGCCCACGUGGGUGUGGGAAUCAGUGGGAAUGAAGGCAUGCAGGCCACCAACAACUCGGAUUACGCCAUCGCACAGUUUUCCUACUUAGAGAAGCUUCUGUUGGUUCAUGGAGCCUGGAGCUACAACCGGGUGACCAAGUGCAUCUUGUACUGCUUCUAUAAGAACGUGGUCCUGUAUAUUAUUGAGCUUUGGUUCGCCUUUGUUAAUGGAUUUUCUGGGCAGAUUUUAUUUGAACGUUGGUGCAUCGGCCUGUACAAUGUG